GACUGGCUCUUUUCCCUGUGGUGGCUGCUCGGGUGGCAGUGAGCGGACAGCGAGGGGGACAGACACAGGUGGAAGGAACCACGGUGGGUUUCAUUAACAAUGACAGUGGCUCAGGAGAUCCUGAGGCUGAUUAAUUUGCAAACAGCAAUUACUUGGGAUUGCUUGAAAAGAAAGUUCUAGCUUAGAACAGGAACCUGAGGAGGGCUGGCCACACUGGAAUCCAGUGCCCACUGUGACAGUGGAGAGCCAGCAGACGCCACUGGCUUUGAUGGAUGAUGGAGAGGGUCCUGGUGUCUUCUGCCAUUUGUGGGGGGUCCUUGUGUGCUGUGUUUGCAGGCACCAUGGGUCUCCCUGGACGGGGUUCGGUUCCACCCCAGCGCCCUUGUCUUGUUUCAUCGCCCGUGUCCGGGCUGUGUAAGAAGCAUGUCCAUUUGUCCCGAGCGGAGGGUCUCUGCCCCGCCCCUGAGGGAGGCCAGGAGGCCCUUGUUGGAUGCUCUGGCGGGCGGCACUGGGACACGGCCAUUGCACCCGGCCCUGGACACAGGGCGGCCACCGCAUCCGGCCCUGGACACAGGGUGGCCAGGGACUUGGCGGGGGGAGCUCUUCAGAAUCUGUCACAUGCACGUGAAUGCUUUAUGGCUUUGGUAUUCUUCUGUUUAAUUUUAGUAAAACCGCGGCCCGUUGCAAGAAGAGUGUGGGCGUUGGCAGCUUUGUCCCAGGUGCUGCAGGGUUGGGGUGGUCCCUGUCACCGCCUGCUGCUGGUGGGGGUCAGCUGCACGGAUGCACGGCCUCGCACCAGCGGCAGCCCCAGAGGCCAUGCAUAGGGCAGGCCCCGGUGGUCAGGGACCCACCCAGUCCUGCCAGGCGUUGGGCUUGGGAUGUGCGGCCGGCUGGGGGCACACAUUCAUGCCGCAGGUCCCCGUGAGUCUGGGCCGUGUGCCUGGCGAGCCCUGAAUUCCACCUCACGUCAGCCGCUGGUUCACGUCAGCCGCUGGUUCACGUCAGCUGCUGGUUCACGUCAGCUGCUGGUGUUGAGUGUUCGCAUGAUGCUUUUCUUUCUUGGGGGAUGGAUCAGUGGAUGGAGAAAUAAAGCUGUGAGGGCAUAAAAUCAAUGUUUGUUUAUAUUGAUAAUCAUCCCUUAAACUCAGAUCCAGGGGCGUCAAGAGACCUGAGCCCGGCCCCGGUGUGCCGCGCACUGGCCAUGUGUCCGGAGAGGGCUGUGAUUGCGGCUGUCAGCCCUGUCCAUUGGAGCUGCAGCUUGGUAAAUGCACAGAUGGAUUUUGAGAAGGUUUCCCUCUAAAGAUGUGGGAGUCUUUGCACCUCACCAAGCUGUGCUGGUGUGGCCGUGGCACAUACCGGGCUUUUUACGUCUCUUCUAGGGAGUGAGUCGGUGGGCAUAGGAUGGCUAAGGUAUGGGAAUUUUAAUAGGGAAUUUUCUAGUAAAUGGUUCUGUUAGUAUUACAGCUUAUUUUAGAAAGUAAGGUGCUUUCAUAGAGAACGUUUAAAAUUAUUAAGAGGUAGACAAUUCUUUUAAAAACCUGAAGGUCUUUUUUUUUUUUCUUUUUUUUGAGACAGAGUCUCGCUGUCGCCCAGGCUGGAGUGCUGGAGUGCAGUGGCGCGAUCUCGGCUCACUGCAACCUCCGCCUCCCAGGUUCACGCCAUUCUCCUGCCUCAGCCUCCUGAGUAGCUGGGACUACAGGCGCCCGCCACCUUGCCCGGCUAAUUUUUUGUAUUUUUAGUAGAGACGGGGUUUCACCGUGUUAGCCAGGAUGGUCUUGAUCUCCUGACCUCAUGAUCUGCCCGCCUCAGCCUCCCAAAGUGCUGGGAUUACAGGCGUGAGCCACUGCGCCCGGCCAAAACCUGAAGGUCUUAUAUUGUGGUGUGAGUUUAUAUUUAUUUCCAUCAUUUUAUAUUUGUCAGAUUUUUAUGCAGGGGGGCUGCAUAAUGUCUCCCUGGAGAGCCUCAGCCUCUGUGGAAGAGUUGGGUCAGGAGAAGCCUCUCGGCGGAGGAAGCCGGAGGGAGAAGCCUCUCGGUGGAGGAACCUUCACCCAGAGACCAGCCUGGGGGUCCUUGGCCCAGACGGGGGAGGUGGGAACAUGGCCUUGGGUUCUUUCCUCCUUGCAGUUUGGGUGAAUAAUGUGUGAUGAGGCCUAAGAGGAGAUUUAUAAAGAGUAUAAUCUCUCAGUCUUAGAGAAAAGUGUUUCAAAGUAUGGGUUCUCAGUGUCUGUAUUGAAAAAAUAAAAAAUUCAGUGAAUGGGUAGGUUAUUUUUCGAUCUGAGGGUUAUUUCUAAGCACAUGAUUUAUCUUUAGCACGGGAGGGUGAUGCCCCGCCAUGUCUUUUUAGCUUAGGGACUGUCUUCUGCCGUGAGUUGGCCUCUCUGCCUGUGCACGUGUGUUGCCGGCCCCGGCUCAGCUGUGGCAGAAGUCAGUCACCUGUGGAGUUAUGGAAGUCCAGGCGGCCACCCCAGGCCGGGGCCUCAUUCCGUUAAGUAGGGCCAGGUGUCUGUCCUCUCACGCGUCCGAGGUGGCUGCCGGCGUGCGGGUGUGACUGUCGAUGAGAGCUCUGAGCUGGGAUAUCUGGUGACGGCUGCCCCUGCUUGGUCUUGCGGUGUGGCUGGGGAGAGGAUUACUGGGUGGAAUGUAGCCGUCCGCCUUUUGUGUUGACCUCUUGACCUCCCUUUUGGGAGGCUUAUUAAUGUCAAAAAGUGAAGAUAUGAGGAUGGGAUCGUAAUUUCUUUGUGUUGCUUUCCAGUAGCCCAGGGACCAAGCUGUGGGAACCAGGCCUCCAUGUGCUGGCCCCACCGUCCUCGUGGUGCCUGUGUCUGUCCAGGCUUAGUCCUCAGAUCAGCUGCUUCACCACAUUGGCUGCAGGCUGGGUGGCAGAUGCCCCCAGGAGGAGGAGAAGCAUUUCUUCCCAGGGCUUUGGCCUGUGCUGUGUGCCUGGAACCUUUAGGUGCUGUGGCUUCGCAGACCCGGACGCAGCGUGGAGGCCAAGCGGUGUCUGUACAGGACCCUUCAGUGAUGAGGGUGGCCAGGCUCCAGCCAGGUCCUAGGGAAAGCUCUCCGAGAGCGACGGCUUAAGCAGUUCUGAAAAAUUGCAAAUGAUCUGUGUUCUUGGAGAAAGAAUGGGAGAGAAGCACUCACUCACAAUAAUGUUGCACCUACUGUGUGCGGGUAGGGUGCAGGCAGUGUGGUCCAGUGUGAGCGGGGAGGGUGCUGGUUGAGGGGUUAGUGCUCGGGACGCAGCCUUUGGACCCAGUGCCCUCCCAAAACUCUGCUCAUCAGUGCCCCUGAGCUCAGCAUUGACCCCUGGAGGAACUGGGCGCCUUCCCUGGUCUCAGACUGUAAGCCUCCUCGGGAAGCAGCAGUUGGCUCCUGAUGCAGCUGGCCUCAGAUCCUGUUGGGAGAGCAGGAUUGGUGAGGAACCUGGAGAGGAGUAGGAGGUGCUGCCUGAUAGCAGAGGUGGGUGAUGGGGGCAGAGAGGGUAGCAGGGGCCCAGUUCAGUCCUGUCUGGUUUUCACGUGGAGCUUUUUAUAGAGUUGUGCUUCUCAAGCCUUUCAAAUGCCUCACAGCGGCAGUCCGACGUGCAGUCAGUGACAGCUGAGUAGAUUACCACCCUCAGGACUAAAUGCAAAAUCAUCUUCACUGGGUGCAGCAUUUACAGUUUUGGUGCUGGAACCUCCUAACCAGUGUUCUUAGGGGCUGUCUUACCAGUGAAGGGAGCUGCCUGCUGUUGACGCUCCACAGGAGGUUUGCGGCAUGGCUGCCAUCUGUGUUGUGGCCUGGGACUUUCUUAGAGAGUGGGUAAAAGAUGAGUCAUCUCUUGUGUGAUUUAUCAGCUUCACUUGUGCUUCCAGGGCUCUUUGAAGCGUCUCACUUUUUAAUUUCAUGAAGAAACAAAUGUAGUGCAGAGAACAGAAAGCUGCUGUGUGACCUGCGGGUGCCCAGCCUGUGGGGCUUCCUCAUCGCCCCCAUCCAGGCAGAUCGAGUGCCGGCUCUCUGUGCUCUCCAGGAGGUGGCCUUUCACAGCAGGGACGUUCUGUGCUCUUAUUUUAACAACUUUGUCGCCGUGAUCCUGAAGGCGCUGACCUACGACGAGAAGCGGGGUGCCUGCAGCGUGGGCACCAACGUCAGGGACGCCGCCUGCUACGUGUGCUGGGCCUUCGCGCGUGCCUAUGAGCCUCAGGAGCUGAAGCCCUUUGUGACUGCAAUCUCGAGUGCACUGGUGAUUGCUGCGGUGUUUGACCGAGACAUAAACUGCAGAAGAGCAGCCUCUGCCGCCUUCCAGGAGAAUGUGGGGAGACAGGGCACUUUCCCUCAUGGUAUUGAUAUUUUGACCACAGCUGACUAUUUUGCCGUCGGUAACAGAUCCAACUGUUUCCUGGUUAUAAGUGUGUUUAUUGCCGGCUUUCCUGAGUACACGCAGCCAAUGAUAGACCACCUGGUUACCAUGAAGAUCAGCCACUGGGAUGGGGUCAUCCGAGAGUUGGCUGCGAGGGCGCUGCACAACCUGGCCCAGCAGGCACCCGAGUUCAGCGCCACGCAAGUCUUCCCGAGGCUGCUGUCCAUGACACUGAGUCCAGAUCUUCACAUGAGGCAUGGGUCGAUUCUCGCCUGCGCAGAAGUUGCUUACGCCUUGUACAAACUUGCAGCCCAAGAGAACAGGCCCGUCACGGACCAUCUGGACGAGCAGGCAGUGCAGGGCCUGAAGCAGAUUCACCAGCAGCUCUAUGAUCGUCAGUUAUACAGGGGUCUGGGAGGACAGCUCAUGAGACAAGCAGUGUGUGUUUUAAUAGAAAAGUUGUCACUUUCCAAAAUGCCCUUUAGAGGUGACACCGUAAUUGAUGGUUGGCAAUGGCUGAUAAAUGACACUUUGAGACAUCUCCAUCUCAUCUCAAGUCACUCCCGCCAGCAGAUGAAGGAUGCAGCAGUCUCGGCCCUGGCUGCUCUAUGCAGUGAAUAUUACAUGAAGGAGCCGGGGGAGGCAGAUCCCGCAAUUCAGGAGGAGCUGAUCACGCAGUACCUGGCUGAGCUUCGGAACCCCGAGGAGAUGACUCGCUGUGGCUUCUCGUUGGCCUUGGGCGCCCUUCCAGGCUUCCUUCUGAAAGGCCGGCUCCAGCAGGUUCUCACAGGUUUAAGAGCAGUUACCCACACUUCCCCCGAGGACGUAAGUUUUGCUGAGUCCAGGAGAGACGGCUUGAAGGCCAUUGCGAGGAUUUGCCAGACUGUUGGUGUGAAAGCAGGAGCCCCAGACGAAGCUGUGUGCGGAGAGAAUGUUUCCCAGAUUUACUGUGCGCUGCUGGGCUGCAUGGACGACUACACCACGGACAGCAGAGGGGACGUGGGCACCUGGGUCCGCAAGGCCGCCAUGACCAGUCUGAUGGAUCUGACACUUCUGCUGGCUCGGAGCCAGCCUGAGCUGAUCGAGGCCCAUACCUGUGAGCGCAUCAUGUGCUGUGUGGCCCAGCAGGCCAGUGAGAAGAUUGACCGUUUCCGUGCUCACGCCGCCAGCGUGUUCCUGACGCUCCUGCACUUUGACAGCCCUCCCAUCCCCCACGUGCCCCACCGAGGAGAACUGGAAAAGCUGUUUCCCAGGUCCGAUGUGGCCUCCGUGAACUGGAGUGCACCUUCCCAGGCCUUCCCACGCAUCACCCAGCUCCUUGGGCUGCCCACCUACCGCUACCACGUCCUGCUGGGGCUAGUCGUGUCCCUGGGCGGCUUGACGGAGUCGACGAUCCGGCACUCCACCCAGAGCCUCUUUGAGUACAUGAAGGGCAUUCAGAGCGACCCGCAGGCCCUGGGCAGCUUCAGCGGGACCCUUCUGCAGAUCUUUGAGGACAACCUUCUGAAUGAGAGGGUGUCCGUGCCGCUGCUGAAGACGCUGGACCACGUGCUCACCCACGGCUGCUUCGACAUCUUCACCACGGAGGAGGACCACCCCUUUGCUGUGAAGUUGCUUGCGCUCUGUAAGAAAGAAAUCAAGAAUUCAAAAGAUAUCCAGAAGCUCCUGUCAGGCAUCGCAGUGUUCUGCGAGAUGGUGCAGUUCCCCGGCGACGUGAGGAGGCAGGCCCUCCUGCAGCUGUGUCUGCUCCUCUGCCACCGUUUCCCGCUGAUCCGGAAGACCACGGCCAGCCAGGUGUACGAGACAUUGCUCACCUACAGUGACGUCGUGGGCGCGGAUGUGCUGGACGAGGUGGUGACUGUGCUCAGUGACACUGCGUGGGACGCGGAGCUUGCAGUGGUGAGAGAGCAGCGCAACCGUCUGUGUGACCUUCUGGGCGUACCCAGGCCCCAGCUGGUGCCCCAGCCUGGUGCCUGCUGAAGCCAGUCCUGGAGCCCAUACCUCACCCCUGCCUGGUGAGGAUGUCUUGUUCCUGAGGGAGGCCGGUGUGGAAAGCCUCGCACAGUGGUGCCUCCAGCUGUUGAAGGGUAGCGCUGGCCCUUGGAGGCUGGCACUAGCUGACAGCUUUUCCUCUCUGCACCUGCGCUCUGGUGACUUGGGGUGGACGCCUCUGCCUUCACUUGAACACAAAUGUGCUUCCUAUAAAAUCAUGUACCAAGAAGUUCCUGCCUUUUGUCUCUGAGCCUGAUGUGUGUAGGGGUGAUGGAAAGGCUCACUGCCCAGGGGUCAGCCAGAGGGGAGGUGGGCUGCACUCCUCCUGCCUGGAGACCAGGCCCCCUUCUUGCCUGGUGCUGUCCCUGCUGUGGGAGACGUCUGGCCACAGGCAGUGCCCCACCCAGUCUUGGAGAGAGAUGAAUGUUAAAUCAGAGGUUCAAAUGCUAGAGAACUGAGAAGCCCUGGUGGCAGGCAUGGUCUGGAGUGCUGGGCAGAUGCUGUUUCUGGGCCCGUCUGCCUGGUGGGGGUGCUGUCCUCCCCCCUGUGCACACGUGAGCAUCGUGCAUGUGGCCCCUCUGCAGUGCAGGAGUCACUGAUUGAUGGGUGUGCCGACCAGCAGCUUCACAAAUGUCUGCUGCAAGGGGAAUCGUCAGAGUCCAAUGUGUGCCUCUACAGUAAUGUCGGAAAUAAAUACCAUUCUUGAAAUAAUUACACUGUCUUAGGAGAGCCUGGGCAGAGUCCACACUUGGGUUUUUAGGCAAAGGGCAGGAGGCUACCUUUGUCUCUGUGUCUGAGCUCGUGCUGAUCCAUCCCAAAGCUGGUGAGGGGAACGUGUAUAAAAAUUUCACUGUGGUAGCAACCCACACCCAUCUCUGGGACCUGUGCUGUGCUCAUAGGGCUUGAGGUGCAGAACCACGGCCAGCAGCACCAAAGCAGCCCCAGGUGUGGCCACUCAGAGGCCCAAGGGCUUGGGUGAGCAACCCUUUCCCUAUGUGAGGAGCCCAGGGGUGCCAUGUGCGUGGUGUAGAUUAGGGUGGCUCCCUGGCCUGCUCUCAGGUGGGGAUGGGGCCUGGACACAGGAACAUGGGCAGGCCGAGAACUGGGAGGUGCCACCGCAUCUGUGAGGCUUGUGAGGUCACCAGGACCACAAGACCAGGACUGUGACAGUCCGUGCUGUGUGUUUAGCAGACAGCUCUUCACGGGAUGUGUGUGACGACCUGGCCACACAGGAGUGUGGGGUUAACACACUACUGUUGUUGUGUUUGACCUGGUGGCCAAUGGUCUUUAUACCCUAAAAGAGCCUUGGGUUACAUUUUUACGAGAUUUAAAUAUUUUAUUCCAACCUGUGUAAUAGGGGUCUCCUCCUCCUUGAACUGUCCCGAUUGGCUGGGGUCACGUGGUGAGGGUCCUGGGUGACCAGGCCUAGCCUUGGCCACAUGAGUCCACACAGUGGAAAAGGCUUGGCUCCUGUGGUCGGCACACACGAGACUCUGGUUGCGCCUGCUGGGUGUGGAACAGGCGCACCAUCGCCAUGCCUGCAGCUCACAAAGCUCCUGCUGGCCUGGGAUGCACUGAGGAUGGAAGGAACAAGUGGCUUCUGAGAAAAACAUGAUGAACUGUUCUUAGUGCAAUUAAAAGAAGAUUCCAGAUAAAUGGCAUUUUAAGACAUGGAGGCAGGUCGAUUACCCACCCAGACCCAUCAGUGACACUAUGUGGCAAAGCAGUUCUUCUUUUAAUGUCGGUCUAACUUAGCAACCCGAGGAAAGUGGAUCACUCCACUGGCCACUGCCUCUUUCCCACUGGAUCCCAUCCAUCACUGGGGCACUUGUGCUCACCAGACACCUGGUGGCCUGGAAAGCCCUCUUUCAGCAGCCGUUUCUGGAGCCCACCAGGGUCCAGGUGAUAGAGUUUGGCAAGGAACCCCUUGCUCACAUGAUAGCUGGGGCAGACAAUAGCAAAUGAACAAGCAAGCACCAUCAAGGCAGGCAACACUGAGUGCUAUGAACAAAGAUAAAGUGGGCAAUGGAAUGGCAUGUUGGGUGUUGACUCCGAGAAGGUGUUCAGAAAACCUCUCUGAAGGGGCAGCAUUUGGGCAGAGGUCCAGACUGUGUCCAAUGGCAGAAAAGAGAAUGCUUGUGGUCCCAGAAGUGGAGCAAGCUUUGUGAGUUUAGAGAGCAGCAAGAAGCCAGUAUCCCUGGGACCGGGGAGCUGAUGUGGGAUUUGUGUACCCACAAACACGUUCUAGGUGCUAACCAGAAACCCUCCAUGUGAGAGCAGAGACCUUGGAGAUCCUGAGGGUUUCUGCUGAGCCCUGGAAUCUAGUCACGCUAUUUUGAUAGCAGAAUGGAUGAGAGAAUUUAAGGCCCAGGGCCAGAUCUAAUGGACCACUAUAUAAAGCUGGGACCCUAAAUAAGUCUUUUUCAAAGGAACAGCAGCAAGACUCUUAUCUCAAUCUAUCUCCCCUGAAGUGGCCUGAAUUAAUACUACCUGUAUGAUCCCCAAAACUCCUAAAGUGGAAAAUUUGAUUGACUUGGCCCUGACCAGUGGUAUUCCCAGACAAGGGCAGAAGAUGCAAAUACAAAACCUCUCUGGUAGAAUGUAGGCUAUAAUAUGAGUACAUUUUUGAAAAGGGCUAGAAAUGAUCAAGAAGAGAUUAGAAAAAAACAGAGCCCCUAGAAAUGUAAGAAGUGAAAUGAAAAGCUCAAUGGAUAGCUUAGACACAGCUGAAGAGAGAAUUAGAAAACUGGAAGAUCUGAAAACAUUAUCCAGAGAACUGGAAGAUAUGACAGCAACAUCAAGAGACAUUGAAGAAUGUCUAACCUUUGGGUAAUUGGGGUCUCAGAAUGAAAUGAAAUGAUGCAGAUAUUCCAUACUGACAUGCAACAGUCCCCAGAUACAGAAGCCUAACAGUCUCACAUUUAGACCUGCCACAGUGAAACUGCAGAACUGUAAGAAGGACAGAGUGAUAUAAACGACUACCAAUUUCCCAGCAGCAGCACUGGAGUUGAGCAGUGAGUAGACCAAGGUCUUCAUUAUGCUGAGAGAAAAUAGCUGUCAAGUUGCUUGAAUUGUGCCCACAGCAUAACAUUAAAGAAGAGAACAAAAUUAAGUCAUUUAGAUAAAAAUAUGCCAUUCUUAUCUGUUUGGUUUUUUAAUCUUGGCUUAAUAUUUGGGGUUGAGUCAUUUGUUUUGAGAGCUGUCCUGUUUAUUGCAGGGUGUUCAGCAACAUCCCAGAUGGAAGCAGCAUCCCCCUACCCAGCUGUGACAAAAAGAAAAAAAAAUGUCUCCAGACACUGCCAAAUAUCUUCUGGGGGUGCCCCUGGUUGAGAACCACUGCUUUAGUGGAUAAACUUUAGGCAGGAGGGAAAUGAUCGCAGUUGGAUAGUUGGAGGAAUGUGGAGCAAGGGAAGCAAUAAACUGUGACCAUAAAAACAUA